AGACAAGAUGGCGACGUCCGUGGGGCACCGAUGUCUGGGAUUACUGCACGGGGUCGCGCCGUGGCGGAGCAGCCUCCAUCCCUGUGAGAUCACUGCCCUGAGCCAAUCCCUACAGCCCUUACGGAAGCUGCCUUUUAGAGCCUUUCGCACAGAUGCCAGAAAAAUCCACACUGCCCCUGCCCGAACCAUGUUCCUGCUGCGUCCCCUGCCCAUUCUGUUGGUGACAGGCGGCGGGUAUGCAGGGUACCGGCAGUAUGAGAAGUACAGGGAGCGAGAGCUGGAGAAGCUGGGAUUGGAGAUUCCACCCAAACUUGCUGGUCACUGGGAGGUAUGGAAGAACAUGGAAAUCCAUGGAGGAGGACCCUAUCUGUCUUCUUCCCCCUGCCGCAUCCCAGGGCUGUGGCUUGUCAUGUGGCACUUGCUUGGGCUGGAUCCAGCCCUGACCCUCUAUUCUGCACCCUGUGAGCCACCGAGACUGAACCAAACCCAGGAAGCGGCGCCACCAACCAGCCUCGCAGAGGCAGAGGCCCUGGAGCAGUGACAGCACAGGAGAUCUGCUGGCUCGGGGGAAGGGGAGGAAAGAGGAAAACAAAGGGAGUGAUCGAGUGAGCCUCGCCCCGCCCUCCCUGCGCCGGCCCAUGAUGUGUCAGUCAGAGGCGCGGCAAGGACCAGAGCUCCGCGCGGCGAAAUGGUUGCACUUCCCCCAGCUGGCCCUGAGGCGGAGGCUGGGGCAGCUGAGCUGCAUGUCCAGACCCGCUCUGAAACUGCGCUCCUGGCCCUUGACCGUCCUCUACUACCUCCUGCCCUUCGGCGCCCUCAGACCGCUCAGCCGGGUGGGAUGGAGGCCCGUAAGCAGGGUGGCUUUGUACAAGUCAGUGCCAACGCGCUUGCUGUCACGGGCCUGGGGUCGCCUCAAUCAGGUGGAGCUGCCACACUGGCUGCGCAGGCCCGUCUACAGCCUGUACAUCUGGACGUUUGGGGUGAACAUGAAAGAGGCCGCUGUGGAGGACCUGCAUCACUACCGCAACCUCAGCGAGUUCUUCCGGCGCAAGCUGAAGCCGCAGGCCCGGCCUGUCUGUGGCCUGCACAGCGUGAUUAGCCCAUCGGAUGGAAGGAUCCUCAACUUUGGGCAGGUGAAGAACUGUGAGGUGGAGCAGGUAAAGGGGGUCACCUACUCCCUGGAGUCGUUCCUGGGCCCGCGUAUGUGCACAGAGGACCUGCCCUUCCCACCAGCCGCGUCGUGUGACUCCUUCAAGAACCAGCUGGUCACCCGGGAAGGGAAUGAGCUCUAUCACUGUGUCAUCUACCUGGCCCCUGGGGACUACCACUGCUUCCACUCCCCCACCGACUGGACUGUGUCCCACCGGCGCCACUUCCCAGGCUCCCUGAUGUCAGUGAACCCUGGCAUGGCUCGCUGGAUCAAAGAGCUCUUCUGCCAUAACGAGCGGGUGGUCCUGACGGGGGACUGGAAACAUGGCUUCUUCUCACUGACAGCUGUGGGGGCCACCAACGUGGGCUCCAUUCGCAUCUACUUUGACCGGGACCUGCACACAAACAGCCCAAGGCACAGCAAGGGCUCCUACAAUGACUUCAGCUUCGUGACGCACACCAAUAGAGAGGGCGUCCCCAUGCGUAAGGGCGAGCACCUGGGCGAGUUCAACCUGGGCUCCACCAUCGUGCUCAUCUUCGAGGCCCCCAAGGACUUCAAUUUCCAGCUGAAAACAGGACAGAAAAUCCGCUUUGGGGAAGCCCUGGGCUCGCUCUAGAGUCUCUUUCCUGAUUAUGGCUGCUAAGGGAUCUUUUCCAAACAGAGUGAGGGUCUUUUCAAGAGGGAGGCCCAUGAGGCCAUCCAGGUAAGGGCCUGCCUCAGCGUGGUUGGGAGUCUGACCAGGUAGGACUUGAAUGAUUCGGCUACCACCUGUUCCAGAGGUGCAGACAAGAGGUGGCGAGAGCCCCCAUCAUGCCCCUCAACCUAUCCCGUUCCUUCUGCCUACAAAUAAAAAGUGCAGGCUGGAAUGAUCUCAGUCACAUUUGGAUCUUUUUAAACACUGUAUAGACGGAAGAGCCUGCAUUCCUGACCGAACCUUCAGUUGGUCUCGGUUGUCGUUUUUUCUUGCUGCUCCUCCCCCCAUCACCUGAGCUGUUUUCUGUUGGCCCCUUUUGUUUUUUGGCCUUAACGCUCCUGCUGCACAGGGUGAGGUGCCUCCUUGGCACAGACUGUGGAUGCCUCUCCCCCAGCAGAGCCACACAGCCUUCGUGACAACUGCUUUCCGUUCCCACAUUCACCUCAUCCUGCUCUUUAGAAAAAGCAGUCUUUGUGCUUGUGGCUGAACGCAUCACCCUGGACUCUGCUAGUGUCUUCUGAGGACACUGAUGACACUGAUUAAUGAUACAGACCUUUGCAGGACCUGAUGAGUGACCCUUCUGGAGCUGGCCAGGUCCUCUGCAGCAGGCAAGACCAAUCAAUCACUGAACCUGCCUCAUGGCACCAGAGUGAACAGGGCAGGCAGGUAGUAGGCCCAGCUGGGGAAAUGGGAGAGUUCCUGUCCCCCUCCACAUAUCCCUACAUGAAAUAUGGGAAAGUUGCUGCUAUUGAUUCAGGGUCUGUCUUGGAGGCAGAGGACCCUUGGUGGAUAGUUGGUCAGUGCCUGGAAAACCUGUCCCAGUUUAUCAGGAACGCAGGCCUGGGGAGCCCCCAGUGGCGGGGACAGGGCCAGAUUUCAUGUUGACCCUGGGGAUGCUGUGAAUUUCUCCUGCAGGAGAGACAUCAUUGAAUUUUUUCAACUGUAUCAGUAGCACAGUAUUUUUGUAUGAAAAGUGGGAGACUUCUGAACAGUAAUUCAUUUAAUUGCAAAGCAUUUUGAAAUAAAAAAAAUCAAACUUAAAA